UGGAAGAGCUGACCUUGGAGCAGAGCAUUGCCGAGUAUCUGAAAGAUGUCAAUGACCCUCGCUGCUGCUCGGAGACCUUGGGGAUGACCUGCACCCACUAGCAUGCCUGGAUGGUUCAAAAAGGCGUGGUAUGGGCUGGCGUCUUUACUCAGCUUCUCCUCCUUCAUCCUGAUCAUCGUUGCCCUGGUAGUGCCCCACUGGCUGAGUGGGAAAAUCCUUUGUCAGACUGGAGUGGAUCUGGUCAACGCCACAGACAGAGAGCUGGUCAAGUUCAUUGGGGACAUUUACUACGGGCUCUUCCGAGGGUGUAAAGUGCGGCAGUGUGGGCUUGGGGGCCGCCAAUCCCAAUUCACGAUCUUCCCACACCUGGUGAAGGAGCUCAACGCAGGCCUUCAUGUGAUGAUUCUGCUGCUCCUCUUCCUGGCCUUGGCCCUGGCUCUGGUCAGCAUGGGCUUUGCCAUUCUUAACAUGAUCCAGGUCCCGUACCGGGCAGUCAGCGGUCCUGGGGGCAUCUGCCUAUGGAAUGUCCUGGCAGGCGGCGUCGUGGCGUUAGCCAUCGCCAGCUUCGUGGCUGCGGUGAAAUUUCACGACCUGACGGAACGAAUCGCCAACUUUCAGGAGAAGCUCUUCCAGUUUGUGGUGGUGGAAGAACAGUAUGAAGAGUCGUUUUGGAUCUGCGUGGCCAGCGCUUCGGCCCAUGCUGCAAACUUGGUCGUGGUGGCGAUCAGUCAAAUUCCCCUCCCUGAGAUUAAGACCAAAAUCGAAGAGGCCACGGUCACAGCUGAGGAUAUCUUGUAUUAAUAGCCUUCCCCUGUUCACAACC